UGCUUUCCUCCCUGCAGGGUGGCCCUGGCCCCCUUGCCAGAUUCCAGCUGGCCGUCAGUGCUCGCGUGUCUCUCUGAAGAGGCUCUGCGGUUCUGGUCCCUGUGCCUGAGCUCCAGGUGCCGCCAGACAUUAUACAACGUGAAGGCUGAGAUCUUUCCCCCUUCGGGAAUGGAGUAUUGCAGAACAGGCUCCCUCUGCUCCCUGGAGGUUUUGAUCACGAGGCUCUCAGACCUCUUGGAGGUGGAUAAAGAUGAAGCACUGACUGAAUCUGAUGAGCAUUUUUCGACAAAGCUUAUGUAUGAAGUUGUCGACAACAGUAGCAACUGGGCAGUGUGUGGGAAAAGCUGCGGUGUCAUCUCCAUGCCAGUGGCUGCUCGGGCCACUCACAGGGUCCACAUGGAAGUGAUGCCGCUCUUCGCCGGGUAUCUCCCCCUGCCCGACGUCAGGCUGUUCAAGUACCUCCCCCAUCAUUCUGCACACUCCUCCCAACUGGACGCUGACAGCUGGAUAGAAAACGACAGCCUGUCAGUAGACAAGCACGGGGACGACCAGCCGGACAGCAGCAGCCUCAAGAGCAGGGGCAGCGUGCAUUCGGCCUGCAGCAGCGAGCACAAAGGCCUACCCAUGCCCCGGCUGCAGGCACUGCCGGCCGGCCAGGUCUUCAACUCCAGCUCGGGCACACAAGUCCUGGUCAUCCCCAGCCAAGAUGACCACGUCCUGGAAGUCAGUGUAACAUGACAACGCCAGGGUGAACACACGCCACUUCCCAGCUAGGAGUGCACUUUAUGGGACUGUGACUGGACUCUUCCGUUCUGGCUCCAGCCAGACCUUCAGUGGUCCUGCCUGGCCGUGGGGACAUCAGAGAGUGUCAUCACGCAGCUGGCCAGCUGAGUUCUGUUGUUGUUUUCAUGCCGCCUGUGAUCUCAGAUUCCUGCUUUUCUCACCCCGUCCCCAUGCUGGUGUCCGACGCCGCUUACUCAGAGCCCUGGCCUCCCUCCCCCUACCUCACACGCUGCUCAUGAAAGUUUCCACCCACGCUGUCUCCACGGAACAGCCUCCGUCUGCUGGCUCUUCGUGGAAGGCCAUUUGUCUUUCAGGUAGACACUCAGCAGCCCUCACGGUCUUAGUGACGUGUGUGCCUUUCUGGUCACACAGCUGCCCAGUUUCCUGAUCGGGGUGGAUUUGUGUCCCCUAAGGGGUAAAACAGCCGUUUACCGCAGAUCCUCUCAUUGUGCUUUUCUAGAAUAACACCCUUCUAGGGGAGGCGGGUGGGGGAGGGAGGGAUCAUAACCCCUUCUGUGCCUUGGGAUGCCGGAGCUGGGGGACCUGGAGGCCCAUCAGCCGGAGCCACGUGAAAGGUACUGAAGAAAGCUGAGACCCGGCUGUGAGGAGCGCCUCAGCGGUGAGGUGGUUUAGGGAUAAAUGUUUCUGGAACCCUGUGGUCCCCCAUAAUGUUGAUAGAAUAUCAUAUGCACUGGGAGUUAAAUAUAUUUAAUUUAAUGAUCAUUAUAUAUGUGGGGGUUAAUAUGUUGUUUUUCUGUCCCUUUAAAGUCUUUACAUGUAAUUGUAGCUGUAUAAUCGUUAUUUUUCUUUUGCAUCUUAAGUCUUAGAAAUUAAGAUAUUCCAUCGUGAGGAUGAGAGAGGUCCUCAGUGUGUUUUUGGUCUGGUUGUAGGGAAGGACUCAAGUCCUGGAAUGUCCUCCACUGGUCUACUGAGUUGCAGUCACACUGUUCCAAUGGAUUAUUUGCUUUCGGUUGUAAAUUUAAUUGUACAUAUGGUUGAUUUAUUAUUUUUAAAAAUACAGACUAACUGAUGUAAUGUUUAUGUAUAAGUUGCACCAAAAAUCAAGGACAAAAAUAAGUGUGUUUGUUUUUACAGGUGUGAAAGUCACAGCUUGUAAAUAAGUGUUGUAUGUAUUAAACCUUUUCCAGUUCUCCAAAGCGAUGUAUUUUUGUACACUUGAAAUAGAGUACUCUUAAUUUACUGGGCAAAUGUGCUUGGAAUUGAACUUGACAAGAUUAGCUCAAGCAGAUAGAGUCGGGUCCAGCAGUGGGUGGCCCUCGUGUGAAUCCCCGUGGAUGUGCAAGUUGUGGAGAGAAGGAGCACCGGGUUCCUGCCCAGCACUGUGCUUGCGGGAGGCGGUGGGGCAUGGGAGGAAGGAGGCACAGACCGGGGAAAUAUGACAGCCGUCAUUUCCAGUAUUCUCUGUGUUGUCUUUUAGCUCAUUCAAUAAAUAAAGGUGGUGUGAUUUUUUUUUCCUCCUGUCUUUUUCAUUUGUAGAAACUGGAGACGUGUAAAGAAGAUAAAUAAUUGUGUAAUUAAACUUUCCAGAAAUUUAUCUUCCUCAUGUGCAGUUUAACAAACUUGGUCAAACUAGUUAGCAAAUUAGAACUUCAGAAUCUAAUGAUAGUUUAGGGUUUCUAAAAUAAGGUUUUUUAUUGUAAAAAUUGACGAUUGCCCUGCAUUUCUACCAAGUCCUGUGAAUAAAGAGAUGGGAGAUUUGAUUCCGUCAGAAGAGACUGUAAUCCGUGUCGUCAGCCUGGGAGCCUUCCCCAGUGUAAUGUAGCUUUCUCUCUUACCUUCUGGAAGAGGGAAUGUUUCAUUUAUUACUGUUUGAUUUUCUUGUAUCUGGUUCUACUCCCAGGAUGAAAUUAUCCAACUACAUAUAUAUUUAGAGGAAGAAAGUGAAGGGGAAAUUUAAAAUGUUUACGGCGCUUAAUUGCCUGGAAAUGAAAUGAAAUCAAAUUUAUCAGUUUUUUUCCCCCUAAUUACCCAAAAGAUCUUUUGCAAACUAUGUUACAUGAAUGCUUCUGCCUCUUUAAGACAAAGAAGAAUGUCACCCAAAAUUGUCAUUUUUUUCUUAAUGUUCAUCAUAAAAGUCCUAAAAGAGUAACUGUAAUUGGAUGUUUAUUGUUUUUAUCUAAAGUAAGGUGUAUGUGUUUGAGACAAGCUGGUUUUGUUGAUAAAGAGAUGUUAAAUAAUUGUGAAGCCAGAUAUGCAAUGUGUAUCUAAAAAGCAAGGAAUUUGCAGCCGUUUUACAAAUAUCUGUGGAACAUGUAAAUACUGUCAAAUGGAAAAUAAAAUAAGUUAUAAUUUUUGUGAAUUUCAUGGGAUGUCCUAUGAUUGGAAAAAUUAUAACUCUUCUGAUUCUAAUGUGGAAAUUGUUGUAUUUAAUCUGAAAAUGACUUUACCUACAACAGUUCCAUUGUCAGCACAGCCUAGGAGGGUCAGAUUCCUGUAUUAAUUACUCUUAGUGGAGAUGCCAGAUAUCCCAUACAGAAUUAGCAGAGAAAAUACACACAGGCUUCUAUUCAAAUUUUCUUUAGUGCUUAAAAUUAAGUUUUAAAAUGAAAUCAGACACUGCAGGUUUGUAUAUAAAAUGAAAAGCUAUACUACUUUUUAUAAAAGGGCAAACUGGGCUGAUGUAAAUGUUUUACUUUCAACUGUGUUCUUUAAAAUAAAUCCUACCUGGUUUUUAAAUUUUA